AGUCUUCGCCGGCGCAGUCACCGCGCAGGGCGGCCGCCCGGAGGUAGCUACCACGGCCUGUGUCAACGACUAAAGCUCCAGUACAGCGGCGCCCUCAGACAGCUGGGAGGGUGGCUCUGGCCGGGAGCGGCGGCCGGUGAGCUACCGCGAGGAGGAGCGGCGGAGGCGACCUCGGCCCGGCCCUGCACUGGCCGCCCGGCAGGCGCGACAUGAGCCUGGUCUGGCAUCCGCGGGAUGCUCCUUAAGCCCCUUCUCCGGCUGUUAACCUCCGGGGAACGGUUGUGACCACACCGACACGUAUUUUACAGAUAAAUCAUUCUUGCGGCGGCGGGUCGAACACGUUUAUUUAUUUUUUAUUUUCUCAACAAGCUUUUACCCAGCACCUGUCCAGUGAAACAACUUGAUAAUCGUUUCGAGGGGCGUCCGCCGGGUUAGGAAGCCACUGCCUGGCAGCUUGUGGAAGCCUCAUUUGCAAAGCCACCCCUCAGAUGUUUUGAAGAUCGUGACGUCUUGUAACUAGCAGUGUGUGCACAGAAUCCUACUCAAGGAACGUCUUGGCCCAGCGAUGCAAAGAACUGAAGUUUCAAGGUUUUAUGUCUAUUGCUGGAUGGUCGGGGUAGCCCCAGUAACUGGGAACUGCUCCGCAGUCCGCUCACGUGGACCCCUGUGGGAAUAGCAAGGUCAGGACAUGCCCUUCUCUCUCCUCUUCCAGCCUGUCCAGUGUUUUCCUUAAGGAAGAAGCCAUCAGAUGUCAUUGCUUCUGCAACUCCUGGGUUAGAGGAGGAGACAGAACAAGCACAAAGAAGGGGAGGGCAGGGUGGCUUUGGUUUCUUGAACAGUAAUUUCCUCAGUCGUCCUUAUUCAUGCAGAAUAGUUUAAAGUCCCUGAAGAUAUUCCCGAUCUCCAGCCGUGAUCGGAGGCCAUGGAUACUGGAGUGUCUCUGGAGUGACCUGAUUCACCCAGCCCUCCUUCUAAGAAAUGCUGUCCUUCUCCUCUCCCCUGACUAGACAGUCCUUGCUUCACAGCGGUGGAUUUUCUUUCGUUCCCGUUCACUUUCAGGGAUCUCCCCGUUAACCAGUGAAACUGUACAUUUGUUUUACAGUUUGUUUACUAAUGAAAACAGGUAACAGCCGGAGUUGGCUGACAUUGGAAAUAGGAGACAAGCUGGAAGAGCCUGUAUUGUCCUCACAAUAGUAUAGAAGAAUUCAAGAGAGGAGAGAGAGACAGCACCGAAUGAAGACUGUAAAAGAAAAGAAGGAAUGCCAGAGAUUGAGAAAAUCUGCCAAGACUAGGAGGGUAACCCAGAGGAAACCGUCUUCAGGGCCUGUUUGCUGGCUAUGCCUUCGAGAACCUGGGGAUCCCGAAAAAUUAGGGGAAUUUCUUCAGAAAGACAAUAUCAGCGUGCAUUAUUUCUGUCUUAUCUUAUCUAGUAAGCUGCCUCAGAGGGGCCAGUCCAACAGAGGCUUCCAUGGAUUUCUGCCUGAAGACAUCAAAAAGGAGGCAGCCCGGGCUUCUAGGAAGAUCUGCUUUGUGUGCAAGAAAAAGGGAGCUGCUAUCAACUGCCAGAAGGAUCAGUGCCUCAGAAACUUCCAUCUGCCUUGUGGCCAAGAAAGGGGUUGCCUUUCACAAUUUUUUGGAGAGUACAAAUCAUUUUGUGACAAACAUCGCCCAACACAGAACAUCCAACAUGGGCAUGUGGGGGAGGAAAGCUGCAUCUUAUGUUGUGAAGACUUAUCCCAACAGAGUGUUGAGAACAUCCAGAGCCCGUGUUGUAGUCAAGCCAUCUACCACCGCAAGUGCAUACAGAAAUAUGCCCACACAUCAGCAAAGCAUUUCUUCAAAUGUCCACAGUGUAACAAUCGAAAAGAGUUUCCUCAAGAAAUGCUGAGAAUGGGAAUUCAUAUUCCAGACAGAGAUGCUGCCUGGGAACUCGAGCCAGGGGCUUUCUCAGACUUAUAUCAGCGCUAUCAGCACUGUGAUGCCCCCAUCUGUCUGUAUGAACAAGGCAGAGACAGCUUUGAGGAUGAAGGGAGGUGGUGCCUCAUUCUGUGUGCUACAUGCGGAUCCCACGGAACCCACAGGGACUGCUCCUCUCUUAGAUCUAACAGUAAGAAAUGGGAGUGUGAGGAGUGUUCACCUGCUGCAGCCACAGACUACAUACCUGAAAACUCAGGGGACAUCCCUUGCUGCAGCAGCACCUUCCACCCUGAGGAACAUUUCUGCAGAGACAACACCUUGGAAGAGAAUCCGGGCCUUUCUUGGACUGAUUGGCCAGAACCUUCCUUAUUAGAAAAGCCAGAGUCCUCUCGUGGCAGGAGGAGCUACUCCUGGAGGUCCAAGGGUGUCAGAAUCACUAACAGCUGCAAAAAAUCCAAGUAACACCUUCUGAGUAGCUGCUGUCCCACACAAUAGGGUAUGAAGCUGCGCUCCUCCAUCGGGUUUGGGGAGGGAGCACUCUGGGACUGUGAGACAAGGAAGCAGGGCCAGCAGUGAGACUAUGAGCCAAGCAAAGAGAAGUCUCAGUGGAGCAUGAGGAGGGAGCAGUCCAGAUGCCAACAAGGAAAUGCGUUUAUGGCUACAAGAGUGCCUCUGCUUUCUCCUCCUCUCCUCCCACCAAGGAUUCUUCCACCUUAAUCUUGUUUUCAUAUGCCUCUUCUUACUUCACCCAUGUUUGUUGUUAUGCAAAUAAAGGUUUUCUCUCCA